UGACACGUGUCAAUCAACCCCCCUCCGGGGGGCGCGCGCUCCGGGGCUCGCGCCGAGGGCUCGCGCCCCUGCCUCGUGCCUGCGCUGCUCGUAUGUAAAUGAGGGCGCGUGACGCGGGACGCAGAUGGACAAGGGAAGAGAGAGAAUGGCCGCUGCCGCCGCCGCUGCUGCCGCCGCCGCCGCCGCCGCUCAGUGCCGGAGCCCUCGGUGCGCGGCGGAGAGAAGAGGAUUCCGGCGGGAACUCGACUCUUGGCGCCACCGCCUCAUGCACUGUGUUUUGAGAGUAUUUUAGAAGGGCUUUAUGGACCACGGCUACGAAGAGACCUCAGUUUAUUUGAAGACUGUGAACCAGAAGAGCUGACUGACUGGUCUAUGGAUGAAAAAUGUUCAUUUUGUAACCUACAGAGAGAAGCAGUCAGUGAUUGUAUACCAUCUCUUGAUUCUUCACAGUCAACACCAACAGAGGAGCUAUCAUCUCAGGGCCAGUCCAACACUGAUAAGAUUGAAUGCCAAGCAGAAAAUUACCUAAAUGCACUCUUUCGAAAGAAAGAUCUUCCUCAGAACUGUGAUCCUAACAUUCCCCUAGUUGCUCAGGAAUUAAUGAAAAAGAUGAUACGUCAAUUUGCGAUUGAGUACAUUUCAAAAAGUGGUAAAACUCAAGAGAAUAGAAAUGGUUCAAUUGGACCAAGUAUAGUAUGUAAAAGUAUCCAAAUGAAUCAAGCAGAAAACUCCCUUCAGGAAGAGCAGGAAGGCCCCUUAGACCUCACUGUGAAUCGAAUGCAAGAACAAAAUACUCAGCAAGGGGAUGGAGUGUUAGAUCUCUCUACAAAGAAAACCAGCAUAAAAUCUGAAGAGUCAUCCAUAUGUGAUCCUUCUUCUGAAAAUUCAGUGGCUGGUUCAACUGUUGAUGCAAAAUCAGAGGAAGCUACUAAAAUGGAAAAAAGAAAAUCAGCAUUAAACAAAGUUUUGGAAUCUUUGUGCAUACAUCACCAGCAACAAGUUUUGGCUAUGUUGAAAUUUCUAGUCCAAGAGCAGAAUGCUGCUUCUCUUUGCUGUUGUAAUACAUCAUGUGUUGUGUCUUCAGAAUCUCAAAAGCCCUUAAUCGAAGAUGAUUUAUGUGGUCUGUUCUGUAGUUGUGAAUAUAGGCUGGCAGAAAGAGGUUGUUUACAAAACGAAAAACAAAGCCCUGGUUUAGAACCUCUGCCAGUCUGUAUUAAAGAUUUACAUUGUUUAUCUUGCCAAACUGUAACUGUUGAACACGUUAAGCCAGUAGUGAAUAGAGGAAUUGCAGACAGUUAUAAUUCUCACAGGUGCUGUUCUGGACUGUUACCAAACAUUCACUCUACAAAAUCAGCCUUUCGUAGUCCUCUUUUGUCAAAGGAAGUAUGUGAUCUUUCAGUCACUCUUAAAGAUGCCUGUAGAUCUCGAAGUCCCUCACCCCCACCAUUAUCACCUAUAGAAACUGAAGGAUUUGAAAAAUUGAAAGACGUCAUCUCAGAGAUUUCAGCCUUAGAAAAUAACAAACUUGAAGCAAACAUUAACCAGCCUCCAUCUCUCACACCAGCAGAAAUCAGCAGCAAUAAGAGUGAUCAUCAAGAUAAAAUACUUAAAACUAAAAAAUCCAGUAACUCUUAUUCUUUACUCUCAAAUGACAGCAAUAAUUCUACUACAAAUCAUGAAAAAGGUGAAACUGCUGUAAUUUUUCAAGAUUUAAUGGAUCGCAUUAAUGAAAAACUAAAAUCAAUAGAAACCACGGAUAUGACAAGCCUUGUAAAAUUAUCUAGCAGUGAUUAUAAUACAUAUAAUGAUUUAAAAUUGGGAGAUUUCAUAACAUCUCUCUUGCAUAAUGCAAAAGCCAGUGAUUAUAGUUUUAUGGAAUUAUUGAGUCAACAUGAUAAAAAGGUAGAAAAUAAAAUUAUUCAGACAAGAUUUCGAAAGCGUCAAGAAACUUUAUUUGCAAUGCGCAACUCCUCUGAUUCACCCAUGUUUAGAAGGCAGUCUUUACAGAUAAAAAGAGAACUUGCUAGUCUUGAUGAAAAUUUUACAAGAAAAAAAUACACCGAAAAAAGUUCAAGGAAAUUGACACAAAACAAUGAGAUAUCUUCAUCAGACAAAGGAGAAUUCUAUCAUGACCAAGGGCCUUCUUUACAAAAUUCUAAAAGACUUCAAGGUAAAAAUCAUGCUGAAACAUCAUUUUCACCAAAUUAUGCAUUACAGUCACUGCAACUACCUCUUCAUAGUUCAGAAACUAACUUGUCUUUUAAUGAAUUUUCAGAAAGCUUUAAAACAACUUCCCCUGAGAAAAUGAGCAUAAGAAAGCCACAGGAGAAAUCUGCAGAUGGAAAACAAUUUUUGCAAAAUGAUAGGAAAAAUCCAAAGUUAGGUAAUACUCAAACUCUUUUGAGAAAUGAUGUUUCUGGACUUUUGAGCAGAACUAAACGAAAUAUUGUGCCUCCAGGGUGGUAUUCUGUAUAUGUAACAAAUAAUUAUGUUUUUAAAAAAUCCCCUAAAGCCAAAAAAGUAUCCGAAUCCACAACAAAAAACGAUCCAGUGAAAAAUAUUCACAUUGAAAGCUCACACAAUAUAGACCUAAACAAAAUUGCAAUGAAUUCUAAUUUACAAGUGGUUGUGAAGCGUUUGGAAGAUACAAUAAGUAUAGCCAAAAAAUCCUGGAAUAAUCAGCCAUUAUCAGAAGGAUAUAAAGCAUCCAAGAAAUUGAUAGAAAUUGAUGGUAAAGACCAACAUGCUGACAGAAAUAUGACUCUUACUCUAAAUAGAAUGACAUGCAAAGAACAGAGCUUAUCAAAAUCUGUGGUAGCAUCCGGCAAUAUUAUCAAUAGUCACUGCAUGCCUACAGUGGAUUUGAAUAACAAAAGACUUGAAAAUCUGAAAAAGUCAUCUAUUUUAGAUAUGGGUCGCUUGAUUUCCAGUGUUGAAAAUGUACCAGCAAAAUAUGAAGGUACUGAAAGUUCAUCUGUUUCCAACUAUUCUAGUCCUAUCAAACUCAUGUUUUUAUCUGAGGUUAAAAGUAGUGAAGGGGUCAAAUAUACUUUAACUUCAGUUGGCACUUCCCAUUCAAAUGUUGUUCUCCCUUCUGAAAAACCUACAACCCAUCACGUAACUGAAGAAAAAACAGAAACAAAUGAGGAUAUCUCAAAUGCGAACUCUGAAAAUUAUCACUCCAGUCAUUAUGAUACUGAUACUUUUCAAAGAGAACUAAACAAAUUCAGUCAUGCAAAAGAAACUGCAGGAUCCUCUACAAUGUUUAUAGGUGAUAUAAAUAGUGAUAAGCCACAAGAAGAACCUAAGGACAAUUCAAGCAGUGCUACUGAUCCAUCUUUUAAAAGAAAACCAGGUAGACCAAAAAAAAUAGGUCCCCAAGUUGUGAAACAGAUUAAGCGACCAAUUGGAAGACCACCAAAGCCUAAAAUUGAUCAAACAAACAUCACUGUUUGCCAGAAUGAGCCCUUUAGUGCUGGAAGGAAAAGCCCAGAAUGUCUCAUAUCAGAAGUAAAAGAAGGUAUUUAUAAAAAGAGUAUUACAGUAACUGUUAUUUACGGAAGGUCAAGAAGAACUAAAAGGCAUGUUUCUGAAGGAAGGGUAAACAUAAGCAACCUUAUGUCUUUAAACAAUAAUGCUGGUGAUUUUCCAACUGAAUAUAAUAGUCCCAGAAAUAUUAGUGAAGACAAAAUUGACUUGGGUGAAAGAAUAAGUGCUGUAGCAAGCUUGACUACUGAAAGUGAGAUCUUGGGGUCUGGCUUUGAAUAUGUGAGACCCAUCAAGAACAAAUCUGUGAUACCUCAGCCUUCCAAGAACAUUAUUCGACCAAAUCAGAAGCCUUUGGCAAUAAGUAGGAAGCCUGGUAGACCGGCAAAAGUGAAAAUCUCUGGCAUAUCUGUGACUAUUAAUAGAACUUCACCUCAGGAAAGAGAAGUAAGUAUUAGCAGCUGCUUGCCUCCUUUAGAACAGGAUAAUACGUCAGGAAAAAAUCUGCCUGAAGAAAAGUAUGACCAACAGUGCACUCAAAUGGAUAAAAUAAGGCACACUGAAGCUGAUAUAUUUAAAAAUGGAUCAAAACGUAUGAUUGCUACUGUACCUUUGAGACAUUCUAUUAGGGAUAGAAAACCAUCUCUGCAUUUCUUACAUUCAUUAGCAUCUUCUAGCUCACUUAUUUAUAGAAACGCUCUGCUCCAUAAAUCAUAUAAACUGCAUUUGCAGAAAAAUAAAAGUCAGAAGGAAAAACAUAGGCACUCAAAGAUGAAAAUAGCUUACAAAGAUACCCCAAGAAACAGACUUUCGCGGAAUGCAAAAAAGUGUUUGGAAGAUAAUAAAUUAGUACCUAUUUCUGAAGUAUCCUUGGAUCCUAUAAUUUCAUCAAACCCUUUGCUCAGGUGGUGGGCUACUUCUGCUUCAAAUGAUUCCUUAUUAGAGGAAUUAAACAAUAGAUUUGAGCAAAUAACAAAUGCUUGGGUGCAAGUAAGUGGAGAUGAAGCUGAAAAUUGUAUUCAUAAAAAAAGAGAACACAUUGAAAAUGAUCAUUUCAAAGUAGCAAGCCCUUUGGAAACUUGUCUUUUAGAACUUGAAGUUUCACCUGUAAAAAUGCUUUUUCAGAAAAAGUAUGAUUUGAAUGAACUCUGUACUUGGUUUAUGCAAACAACAGAAACACAGUCUCUUUCACUAGUUAGAAAAGCAAAUGCCCGAAACCCUUUGGAAGUAAUAAAUACCAGGGGAAUCAAAUUAGGGACCAAAUAUUCUGACUUUAAUGCCAGCCCCUUCAGAAAGCACUUUAAAAAAUUUGCACUCUCUUCUCCUUCAAAAUCAGCAGAGAAAUUGCAUAUACUGCAUAAAGUGGCUAACUCUCCACUCUUAAAUGUGAAAAGUAAUUUAGCAAUAGCUAGAUUAAAAAGGACUGAGUUUAAGAGGUUGCAUCAUGAAAGGUGGAAAAGAGAGGGAAAGCUGCACAACCAUGGAACAGUUGACUGGAACUCUAAAAGGAGAAACUUAAGAUUUUUCUGCCAGAACCAAUUUUUAAAUAAGACUGAGGGAGAAACAAAUGCUGACAUCCCACUCCAAGGAAAAAGCAUAGUAGAUAAUCAGUGUGUUUUGCCACCUGAGAUCAGGGGUGACUUGCAGCAGAGGGUAGUAAUGCCUGACUUCAAAAUACAUGCUAGUUUUGAGAAUAAAUUUAAGUCAGAAGCAAAAGAGAAUGGAACAAAUUGCAGCCAAAAAGACUUUCAAAAGGGACCAAGACUAGAAAAUGUAUGUCCUAAUAGUUGGAGGUCAAAAACCUUAAAAGACUGUAGAAUAUUUUUGAGGAAGCUCAACUGUCUUGAACACAGAAAUACUUUUAAGCUAAAUACAAUCAUUUACUCUCCUGAAUCUACUGACAGUGGAAAUACUCAUCAGACUCAUAUGGAAGAAUCAAAGCGCUUUACUUUAAGAUCUCAUUCUGCUAGGCAAAAUUCUUUUAAAAAGCAAUCUAAAGAAAUAGAAAAUGCUAACACAAAUAAUCCUUCAGCUGAUGAAUUUGCUGACCAUCUUGGCAAUAGUAAAUUAAGCAAAUGUGUUAACUUUGACAAGAAUCCUGAUAGUUUUGAAGUUCUUAGCAAUUUGAACAAAAGAAAAAGACCACCAUGGAAGAUCACAGAAAUGUCAACAAAAAGACAUAAACGACAGUCUUGCAACAGUGGACAAAUGGCAAACUAUUUUUCCAAAUCCCUAGCAUGCUACAAGUGAAAACUGAUGAGAAACUGAAUGUGUCUGAUGAGAAUACAGCAAGUUGCCCUUUGAGCCCCAUUAAGAUGUGCCUUAAUCGUCCCAUUGAAUGGAAUCUGAAUUUGACAACAGCAUCUCUAACGAGCUGUACAGUUCAUAACCAAAAUCUCAAAAGCGAAGAGAAAUAGAUUGCAGUUCUUCUUGCACUAUCUUUAUUUUGUAUGUCAGUAUUCCUUCUGAACAAUAAGCAUUUAUCAAUUGAUCUUGAAGUAUUUCUAGUCCUGUGAUUUGUCUUUAUAUUAAAUCAUUAGCAUUAAUCAUUUUGAUUAUAUUCUUUAUAUGUUUUUUUUACAUGUUUUACAUCAGAUCAUUGUGGAAUUUUGUAAACGGAUUUUGAUGUUUCUCUUUUAGUGGUAUUAUGUGAAUUUUUUAUGCCCUAAGUUUAAAUACGUAAUUGUCCCUAGUUUUAUUUCUGUGCACAAAGUUUUAAUAUAUAACACAUUGUGAUUUAUAAAGCUAGUAUUGUAAAGAUUUGUGAUGAUAACCUGACCCAUGAGCAGUUGUAAAACAGGUGGAUACCAACUACCUCGAAGCAAAUUGGUGAAAGAAAAGGCAAAGGUAUCUCUUAGAAGUAAAUCUCCUUCAACGUUAUAUAUGUACAGAAGAAAAAAAGUUGAUCAUAGCUUUUUGUCAAGUAGCAUGUUUCCCAUUCACAGGAAAAUGUGAGCUUAUCAGUUCUUUCUCUGUAUUUUAAAUCUAAGUCUGUGGGCUUUAAGAGCAAUGGCACAAUUGCAUGUUUACUGUUCAGCAAAUCUGUGCCUCUUGAUAGAGAAAAAUACUAUGUGGUUUCUGUAAGUUACCAGUUUUGAAUGAAAAAUGGUAAAUGGAUUUACAUCUGUUUUAUUGUACCUUAGCCUUUUAUUUUAAAGUUAAAGGGAUGACUUUUAAAAGCAGGACAUUCCCUACCUUUAAUAGUGCAAAGCACAGUUUCAGCAAUGGCUACAUGACUAUGUCUAAAAACUGAAUACUCAGAAUACUAAAGGUUUGGUGCUUAAAUUUAUUUUUCCCAUGCCAGAGAAAGCAAGCUUUGGUAUGGUAAACCACAUGAGAACAUGGCUCCUUUCUUUUUGGAUAGCCUGGCCAUGUGUGAAUGGGAUUUUAGCUUAUUAUGUUUCUAAGACUUUUCCUUACAGCACACUUAAUGUACCUUUUCAGUCCUUCUCCCAACCCCCUGCAAAUUGUCUUUAAAACAACAACACAUAAGGAAUCUGAAGCACAGGAGAACACAGAGCCAACAAACAGAAUGAAGAACAAUCAUCUAUUUUUAACUGACUUUCUAUCAUUACCAUUUUUCCUUUUGCUUAAUAACUAUCUUGCUUUGAAACUUUGACUCCUUUUAUAAGUUCUAUGAGGCACAUAUGUAUAGCAAUUUGGUUCUAAAAACCAGUGAUCUUACUUUAGCUCCAUCUUAAAAUUUCACCUUAAGUAAAUGGCCUCUAGUAGAUGAUAAGCCUAAAAAAAGCACAAUUAUUAAAACAAACAGAUCCAUGUUAGGACAUUUCUGAAUAAUAAAGAGAAAAGGUGUUUCGUUGGGUAUUGCAGAAAAGAGGACCAAUUUCAUAUAGUACAAGUUUCGUAAGUCAGGCCAAGUGUCAAUUUCAAAAGACAAGAAAUGAAAUUGACAGUGAAUAGUGCUCAUAAAUUGGUAGCGUAUAUAAAGAGAAGUUCCUGUCACAUUAUAUUCCCACUAGAAUUAUUAUCCACAGUAAAUAAAUAUUAUUUUGUUAUGCCAAAAAUAUAGCGAGCAGCUUCAUGGUUAAUAAUACAUUUAUGUUGACACCUCCCUAAUCCAGGAAACAUUCACAAACAAGGACUCCCAUAUACAAAUACUUUAGGAAGAGAGAUUUCCCAGGCAGAUAUCACCAAAAAUGUUUUCACUGUAGGAAUCACAAAAUAAGUUUUUGUCAAAAUAACUGUUGUUGAACGUUAUACUGGUCUUCCUCACUGGUGAUUGAUAAGCUCCUUUCUAGCCAGUUUGUGGUACUUCCUUCAUUUUCCCUAGAAAUGUUACUUGUUAAAUGUGUCCUCAGGCGGUUUCAUCUUUGUUGAUUCUGCCCAUCUAAGUCAUAAGCUUCUCAAAUGCAAGCUACUAGCUAGUUACACUUGUAAGUUUUCCAUAAUGACAUGAUUUUAAACAUAAAGAGUUCAUAAGAAUCACUUGGAGAGACUAUUUAAAAAUGAGAUUCCUAGGCCCACCUCAGAUUGUGAUAAAUCUGUGUGACUGACUGAUGCACACUUUUUCUGGACUAUAAUAACUGAUGCUGCUCUACUGCUUUAAUACAGGCCAAAGUAACGUGGAAGCGCACAGCAGAAAAUCUUCAGAAAGACAUCAGGUUUGUUCUGAUUUUGACAAGGGUAACUUCUUCUUUAUUAAAGCAAAUAACUGGACAUAAUCUUAAAGGAUUCCACCUCCAUCGUCUUUCCUAACUUAGAUCUUCAUUGAGAAAUUGGGCAAGGUUAAGUUUACUUUUUUCUAGUGCUGCGGUUUUGGCUCGUCUUGGUAGUCUCAUCUUCAUUUCUGAUUCUGGUUCUGGAACUUCAUGAUCACUAAAUAGAUGUUGAAAAUACACGAAUUUAGAUACAAGCUUUAAAACCAGUUUAUUUAUAAAUAAAACUUUUUUGUUUCUGACUCACAUUCUAUCAGUGUUUAAUUGAUAGCCUGAUUCCAUUGACUUAGCUUAAAACUAAAAUCUCAAUGUCAAAAAAACACUGACUUGGCUAUCUAGCAAAGUGAAUCAGGGAAAAUCUAGCUAAUGAUUUUAUAUACUAUAACAGAACCUGGUGUUAUACAGGAAAAAAAGCCACAAACUUGUAAUGAAGCUUGUAAUUAAACGAGGACCAUAACUGUCCAAAAGAGAUUUCUUUGAAACUCAAGAAGUGACAAAAAAAUUAAGUUCUCUCUCUUGAUUUAAGCAAUAAAUUCCAAAAACAUAGUAAAAAACAAGUUUCCCCCCAAAAAAGACAAAUUUAAUCAACAGUGUAAAACUAUGUACUGAAAAUACACACAAUACAAUUUUGCAAAUGAAUACAAGACAGCUACCAACUUUCAGCUCUAACAGUGGCUUGACUGACAGAAGCCAAAAAUAAAACACUCUACCACACAAUAUACCCAAAUUAUAGACAGAAUUAUUCUAUCAGUAUGUAAGUGUAGAGAACCCAAAUAUUAUCAAAAUCAAGAGUUUGCUAACUGAAGAUCAAAGAGGAGUCACAUCAUGUAAUUAAAAAUUGAAACAACAUAUUAAAGAUAGUACUAAAGACCAUGCCAGCUAAUAGGCAAAAGCAAACACGCCGUAAGAAGUCAAAUGCUCUUGAUGAUGGAAUUUUAGACUAUAUACCUAAGACAGCUAUUUAUAGUUUUCACUAUCUUGUUAUAUAUUCUCUCUCAUUCGCAAGAAAAUUAGUUUUUUUCUACUUGUAGAAAUAAAAAGUGAAGAUAGGCCUCCAUAUAUUCUAGACAUGCAUGACAUACCUUUCAGAGUCGGCUUCAGCAGUCUGACACCUCCUGUUCGUCCUAGCUGAAACUGUCACUUUUCUCUGUCCUUGAAGAUAGUAUAAUUCAUUAUCAGGAUUUAUUAUCAGUUGCUUUUUGUUUUUAAUCUAGUUUCUAGGCUAACUAAAUCCUUUGUCUUCAACACAACAAUCCUUUCAACACAUGUAUCUCCUACUUGUUCUAGCCAUCUUGGUACCAGUUAUCACUGCCACAGAAAAAGGAACCCAAGCAAGAUUAAAACUUAAUUUAUUUUGUAAGCACUAAUAAUGAGUAAGGGAAAAUAAGGAAAUUUCAAGCAAGUUAAAAGAAGGCAAAUUUUAGUUCAAUGUAUUUGAGGACAGUAUAUGAAAAAUGUGUUAUAAUGAAGUACCUCUAUUAUUGCUAUAGCACAAAGUCUGUGGAGACUCAUGAAAAUUAAGGGUUAGAAAGGUAGGUUAGGUGCAUAAACAGGUGCUAAAGAAACAACUUUUUUUUUUCUUGGAAGGUGAUAAAACAUAGUAAGGUAAUAAUGGCUUCUUGUAAAAUAACAUACAUGACCAAUUCAAAUGUGUUCUAAAAUAUAUUUCAAUGUAAAAACUAGAACCUUUAUAUACUGGGGAUUAUAAGAUUCUACUUACUAGAAAUUUACAAGGUUAAGGAGUAAGACAAAGUUUGGCUUGUGAUGUUUCUCAUUUAUAAGGAAUAAAACAAUAUGAAUAUAUGAAGUUUGGUCUAUUAAAAAGGAUGGUGUUCUCAUGGUGUGAUAUACCACAAAAAAAAUCUGAUCAAAACCAAACUGUUCAAUGUGACAGUCUGAAAAUUAUAUACUCUACUUCAUUCAUGUUACACUUUUUUCUACUCCUUACCUGCUUUUACUAAUGCAUUUAUCCCCAAGAAAACAUCCAACAAUAUGGGACUAAUUUGGAACAAUAUCCAGCAAUUGGUAUUUAAAUAAUUUACUGGUUACAAAACAAUAUUAUGACCAGACUCCAUUUUAGAAAAAAUUAAAUCUGCAUCGAAAAGGGCCUUAAAAAAUAGAUUUCUAAAAUCAAAAUCAUGGUUGGCUCAUGGGUGGGAUUAUUAGUGUUCCUUAUAGUAGUUUGUCUGGAUGUACUUUCUGAUUCUUCUGUAAUAAGCAUGCAUUGCUUUUGUAAUGAGGAAAUAAUAAAACAAUAAAAAGAUCUUGAAUUUCA